ACUGAGGUCCCACCAGAGUGAGGAUGUACAGGGCCGCUUCCCUCCCCAGGCCCUGCUGGGGUUGACACCUUUGUCUCCAGUUUCUUUCCCCAUAGCCUUGAACCAGAGGGGAAGCCAGUCAAAUACGACCCCUCCUUUCGAGGCCCCAUCAAGAACAGAAGCUGCACAGAUGUCAUCUGCUGCGUCCUCUUCCUGCUCUUCAUUCUAGGUUACAUCGUGGUGGGGAUUGUGGCCUGGUUGUAUGGAGACCCCCGGCAAGUCCUCUACCCCAGGAACUCUACUGGGGCCUACUGUGGCAUGGGGGAGAACAAAGAUAAGCCGUAUCUCCUGUACUUCAACAUCUUCAGCUGCAUCCUGUCCAGCAACAUCAUCUCAGUUGCUGAGAACGGCCUACAGUGCCCCACACCCCAGGUGUGUGUGUCCUCCUGCCCGGAGGACCCAUGGACUGUGGGAAAAAACGAGUUCUCACAGACUGUUGGGGAAGUCUUCUAUACAAAAAACAGGAACUUUUGUCUGCCAGGGGUACCCUGGAAUAUGACGGUGAUCACAAGCCUGCAACAGGAACUCUGCCCCAGUUUCCUCCUCCCCUCUGCUCCAGCUCUGGGGCGCUGCUUUCCAUGGACCAACGUUACUCCACCGGCGCUCCCAGGGAUCACCAAUGACACCACCAUACAGCAGGGGAUCAGCGGUCUUAUUGACAGCCUCAAUGCCCGAGACAUCAGUGUUAAGAUCUUUGAAGAUUUUGCCCAGUCCUGGUAUUGGAUUCUUGUUGCCCUGGGGGUGGCUCUGGUCUUGAGCCUACUGUUUAUCUUGCUUCUGCGCCUGGUGGCUGGGCCCCUGGUGCUGGUGCUGAUCCUGGGAGUGCUGGGCGUGCUGGCAUACGGCAUCUACUACUGCUGGGAGGAGUACCGAGUGCUGCGGGACAAGGGCGCCUCCAUCUCCCAGCUGGGUUUCACCACCAACCUCAGUGCCUACCAGAGCGUGCAGGAGACCUGGCUGGCCGCCCUGAUCGUGUUGGCGGUGCUUGAAGCCAUCCUGCUGCUGAUGCUCAUCUUCCUGCGGCAGCGGAUUCGUAUUGCCAUCGCCCUCCUGAAGGAGGCCAGCAAGGCUGUGGGACAGAUGAUGUCUACCAUGUUCUACCCACUGGUCACCUUUGUCCUCCUCCUCAUCUGCAUUGCCUACUGGGCCAUGACUGCUCUGUACCUGGCUACAUCGGGGCAACCCCAGUAUGUGCUCUGGGCAUCCAACAUCAGCUCCCCCGGCUGUGAGAAAGUGCCAAUAAAUACAUCAUGCAACCCCACGGCCCACCUUGUGAACUCCUCGUGCCCAGGGCUGAUGUGCGUCUUCCAGGGCUACUCAUCCAAAGGCCUAAUCCAACGUUCUGUCUUCAAUCUGCAAAUCUAUGGGGUCCUGGGGCUCUUCUGGACCCUUAACUGGGUACUGGCCCUGGGCCAAUGCGUCCUCGCUGGAGCCUUUGCCUCCUUCUACUGGGCCUUCCACAAGCCCCAGGACAUCCCUACCUUCCCCUUAAUCUCUGCCUUCAUCCGCACACUCCGUUACCACACUGGGUCAUUGGCAUUUGGAGCCCUCAUCCUGACCCUUGUGCAGAUAGCCCGGGUCAUCUUGGAGUAUAUUGACCACAAGCUCAGAGGAGUGCAGAACCCUGUAGCCCGCUGCAUCAUGUGCUGUUUCAAGUGCUGCCUCUGGUGUCUGGAAAAAUUUAUCAAGUUCCUAAACCGCAAUGCAUACAUCAUGAUCGCCAUCUACGGGAAGAAUUUCUGUGUCUCAGCCAAAAAUGCGUUCAUGCUACUCAUGCGAAACAUUGUCAGGGUGGUCGUCCUGGACAAAGUCACAGACCUGCUGCUGUUCUUUGGGAAGCUGCUGGUGGUCGGAGGCGUGGGGGUCCUGUCCUUCUUUUUUUUCUCCGGUCGCAUCCCGGGGCUGGGUAAAGACUUUAAGAGCCCCCACCUCAACUAUUACUGGCUGCCCAUCAUGACCUCCAUCCUGGGGGCCUAUGUCAUCGCCAGCGGCUUCUUCAGCGUUUUCGGCAUGUGUGUGGACACGCUCUUCCUCUGCUUCCUGGAAGACCUGGAGCGGAACAACGGCUCCCUGGACCGGCCCUACUACAUGUCCAAGAGCCUUCUAAAGAUUCUGGGCAAGAAGAACGAGGCGCCCCCGGACAACAAGAAGAGGAAGAAGUGACAGCUCCGGCCCUGAUCCAGGACUGCACCCCACCCCCACCGUCCAGCCAUCCAACCUCACUUCGCCUUACAGGUCUCCAUUUUGUGGUAAAAAAAGGUUUUAGGCCAGGCGCCGUGGCUCACGCCUGUAAUCCAACACUUUGAGAGGCUGAGGCGGGCGGAUCACCUGAGUCAGGAGUUCGAGACCAGCCUGGCCAACAUGGUGAAACCUCCGUCUCUAUUAAAAAUACAAAAAUUAGCCGAGAGUGGUGGCAUGCACCUGUCAUCCCAGCUACUCGGGAGGCUGAGGCAGGAGAAUCGCUUGAACCCGGGAGGCAGAGGUUGCAGUGAGCCGAGAUCGCGCCACUGCACUCCAACCUGGGUGACAGACUCUGUCUCCAAAACAAAACAAACAAACAAAAAGAUUUUAUUAAAGAUAUUUUGUUAACUCAGUAAA